GCUUCCGGUCUUAGCUGGACCCGUCUGGGAGGUAGGUUUGUGAGCGUGAGAGAUCGAUCUGUACCGCGGGGAUCCGAAGUAUGCUUAUCCAGGUGGGCUGCCUCAAGCCUCGAUCCCACCCCCGCGCUGGUAGAUGGUGUCAAGGUCCUUGCGUGGGAGAAGGACUUGGGUGAGAUGCAUGCGGAGAUUGCCCCCAAUUCCGGCCUGGAGCCAAGGGAAAGGGAUGCCUGGAUUUGUGUCUCUAUUGGUGGUCCACGCUGCGGAUGCCUGGGUAGCCCAGAGGUUAUCUACGCCAUACUUCUCACUGUUUUUGAGCAUACCUAGAUGUUCCUUUCCUAGGCGGAGUAUAGAUCGCACGUGUUCUAGCCUCUUAGACUCAGAGGGUUCGAGCUCUAUAAGCCCCUCCACUCCCUUCAUUUUACAAAUGAGACUCAAACCUAGAGCGCGGUAAUGACCUUACUAAGACCAAAUGGCUGGUGAAUUGGGCUUCACUAGAAUCCAGGCUUGCUGGCUAACACCAAUGCUCCCUCCAUCAUUUCAUGUUAUGUUUUCAUUUCCCCUCUGUCUGAGAGAUUGCUCUGAUGUCUUUCCUUCCAUAAGUCCUACGGAGAUCGAGCUUACCUCAUUUUUCUCCCAGGCCUAGGAGCUCAAUUACCAGGAUCACUUUCUUCCCCAGGGUGUACUACAGACCUCCACAUGUUGGACAGUAGGAUUCAGCAGAGAAUGAGUCCCACAUCCUCUUUUCAUCCAUAAGCCACUCUUCCCAACUACUCUUCCGCCUUCCAUUGUCCCUAUGUCUACUUUACUGCUCAAUCUGGAUUUUGGGGAACCUCCUCCCAAAAAGGCAUUAGAAGGAAAUGCCAAGCACCGAAAUUUUGUCAAGAAGCGGAGGCUCUUAGAACGGAGAGGCUUUCUGAGUAAAAAGAACCAACCCCCUAGCAAGGCGCCUAAGUUGCACUCUGAACCUUCAAAGAAAGGGGAAACUCCUACGGUCGAUGGCACUUGGAAGACCCCUUCCUUCCCAAAAAAGAAGACAGCUGCUUCCAGCAAUGGGUCAGGACAGCCCCUGGACAAGAAAGCUGCAGUGUCUUGGUUGACCCCUGCCCCUUCAAAAAAGGCUGAUUCUGUUGCUGCUAAAGUAGAUUUGCUGGGGGAGUUCCAGAGUGCCCUUCCAAAGAUCAAUAGCCACCCAACCCGCUCUCAGAAGAAGAGCUCCCAGAAGAAAUCCUCUAAAAAGAACCAUCCUCAGAAGAAUGCCCCACAGAACUCCACCCAAGCUCAUUCAGAGAAUAAAUGCUCCGGAGCAUCCCAGAAGUUGCCACGGAAGAUGGUGGCAAUUGACUGUGAGAUGGUGGGCACAGGACCAAAGGGGCAUGUUAGUUCCUUGGCUCGAUGUAGCAUUGUCAACUACAACGGAGAUGUGCUUUAUGACGAGUACAUUCUUCCCCCCUGCCACAUUGUGGACUACCGAACCAGGUGGAGUGGUAUCCGGAAGCAGCACAUGGUGAAUGCCACACCCUUCAAGAUUGCUCGAGGCCAGGUAAGAAGCAUGGGGCUUGAUGGUGGCAGGGAGGUGGAUGGAGAGAGGUCUAAAUCAUUUUUCAGCAAAGGAUAUCACUAUGGGAAGACACCAACGUUUGUGGAGGGAGGGAGGAGAAUCUAUCAGUUGUUGAAGAAGGCCCCCUGUCGGUGGAAGAAGCAGUGAAAGUCAGGAAGGUACAAUUAGCUGGUGUCACAAACUUCAUUGGUCAAGAUCUAUUUUAGCCGGGCGCAGUGGCACUUGCCUAUAAUCCCAGCACUUUGGGAGGCUGAGGCGGGAGAAUCGCUCAAGCCCAGGAACUCAAGCCCUGUCUGGGCAACAUAGCGGAACUCAUCUACAAAAAAGUUAGCCAAGUGUGGUACAUGCCUGUAGUCCCAGCUACUCAGGAGGUCGAGGCUGCAGUGAGCUGAGAUCACACCACUGCCACUGCACUCCAGCCUGAGCGACAGAGUGAGAUCCUGUCUCAAAAAAACAAACAAAAAAACUAUUUUAGGUUCUAAAUUGGGUCUGGGGAACUGGGAAUCUGCAUAGAAAAAUAACAGCAAGUGAUGAAACUAGACAGAGCUGCAGACACCAGUGUCAGGAGAAAGGGCUUGAUUUGGAAAAACCUUGCGAGUUGGAGCCUAAGCUUGAGAGAGGAAAGGUGGAGAGCUCGUCCCAAGCAAAAAGUAGCCUGGGGCAAGUGCGGAAAGUGGUGGUGGUAAGAGAGGGCAGAAAGUUGACAGGAGGAGCUGGGGUAUAUAUUGUCCAACUGGAACAGGUAACCAGUGAACGGCAUAAACGGCACAGGGCCGGCACUUCGGGUUGUCAUCUCACUCCUAGCCCUGUGCUGGCCAUGGAGCGCAAGGCAUGAACGGAAAGGAGAGUGAGCUGGGAGGGGUGAAAGAGGAAGUGAAGGGAGAGCAAGAGACCUGCUGGUCUCAGGAGGCCGCCAGAGGGCGCCCUUGGUCCACGUCUUUGCAGUUUCAGGUCCACACUCUGCCCUCUCUGGACACGCUGUUCCCAUAAUGCCUUAUAUGCGGUCAGUUGGAGGAGGUUCGUUAGAGGUGAGGUGACUGACUAUUUUAGAAAAGACGGAAAGAAGAGUUAAACAUCUUGUGCACAAAGGGGCGCAGCCAAGCAAAGGCAUAGGAGAGGCAGAAGAUGGGACGGGUCUGAGACAGCAAAUCUGCCCAGCUUUGAUGAGGGCUAUAUGUCGAGGUUAAUAAGAAGUGAAGGUGGUGGUGGACAGUAAGUAGGUGAAGUCAGGAGUAACGAAAUAUCUAGUUCACGGGACUACGUCUGGUUUUCAUCAUAAAGCACUUCCCCAGUGCCAAGCUGGGGUUAUGAGACUAAGGUAUGUCCAGAUGAGCCUAGCCCCUUCAGAGGGGGUCCCUUUGGGAGGCUAUGCAGGACUGUCACUUUUGUUGAAAACCUGUUUGGAACCUCAUUUGGGAAUGGCCUUCAGAGCCUGUGGUGUGUUCUUCGGUUGUCCUCAUUGGUAGCAUGUCCUCCUACUUCAAGAGCCUGAAAUGGCUAGGUGUGGUGACAUGUGUCUGUAAUCCCAGCUACUCAGGAGUUUGAGGUGAGAGCAUUGCUUGAGCCCAGGAGUUUGAGGCCAGCCAACCUGGGAAAAAUAGCAAGACCUCAUCUCUUUUAAAAAAUAAGUUACCUGAAGGCCAGGUGUGGUGGCUCACACCUGUAAUCCCAGCACUUUGGGAGCCUGAAGCGGGCAGAUCACAAGAUCAGGAGUUCAAGACCAGCCUGGCCCAUAUGGUGAAACUCCGUCUCUACUAAAAAUACAAAACUUAGCCAGGCAUGGUGGCAGGUGCCAGUAGUCCCAGCUACUUGGGAGGCUGAGGCAGGAGAAACGCUUGAACCCGGGAGGCGGAGGUUGUAGUGAGCCAAGAUCGCGCCAGUACACUCCAGCCUGGGCAACAGAGCAAGACUCCAUCUCAAAAAAAAAAAACAGUUUCCUGAAAUAUUGAGAAGUUAUUUUUAUUUUACUUGGUUCCAAAACUAGUGUGAAUAAGGUUGCUUCUGCAACUUUAGUUUAUAUGUGAUUCUUAAUUUUUUACGGUUUGUAGACUCUGAGAAUUUGAUGAAAGCCACAGAUUCUCUUCCUCUAGUACCCAUACACAUCUAAUUGCAUGUAAUUUUGGGCUUUUGUUAGCCUCCCUGGAGCCCGGGUCCCAGCCAUGUGUCUAAGGCCAACAUAAUGGUAAUAGUUAAAGGACUUCAUGUAGCAAGCCAGAACUGAACUAAAUACAUGGACAUCUCAAACAUGAGUGUCAUUUAGGACUGAAGGCAAAUUAAUGUCAUGGGGUGGAGAUCAAUAAGAAGGUAAGGAGCCACUGGCAGUAUGAGUCCAAACAGGGUAUACCAUGGAAAUCACCUGUGGAAGAGGAAGGUGGAUUCCAGAAGAAAGAAAACUUGUGGGAGUGAGCAUUUCAAGGAUGGAGAGAUCUUGAAGAUACUCACAGGGAAGAUAGUGGUGGGGCAUGCCAUCCACAACGACUUCAAAGCCCUUCAGUACUUUCACCCCAAGUCCCUCACCCGUGACACCUCCCAUAUCCCCCCCCUCAACCGGAAGGCUGACUGCCCGGAGAAUGCCACCAUGUCUCUGAAGCAUCUCACCAAGAAGCUGCUAAACCGGGAUAUCCAGGUUGGGAAGAGCGGACAUUCCUCUGUGGAAGAUGCCCAGGCCACCAUGGAGCUAUAUAAGUUGGUUGAAGUCGAGUGGGAAGAGCACCUAGCCCGGAAUCCCCCUACAGACUAGUGGCAGUGGGGACGCUGGUGAUAUGAGGAGGCAGAGGCAGCACCCAGGAGAAACAGGGCAGUGGACCAAUGGACAGCUCCACCAGCUCCACAUCUUUGGAAGCUAGAUUUGGGGAGAGAGAAGCUCUACCCCAGACUUAAUACCCAUUGAAAUUUCACCUCAGGUGUUGUGUCCUGUGUCUGGUUAAGUGUCCCAUGGAAGGGGAAAGCCUUCACGUCAGAACCCAACCCUAUACCUUUUACUUCUUAAAUGGUGCUAACCACAGGUGUCCCAGGGUGCUCUGUGCCAGUUAAGAUUUUUAACUUUCAAGGGGCAGGGCAUACUGGGAAAUGUAGUUUCCCAAACUGCCUUAUCACUUGGGUGGACAUAUGUCUCCUUUUAUGCCUUUUGGUCUUGAGUAAUUAACAGCAUCCUCUUCCACGCUCAGAAGUGUUCUGGUUGGGGCCAGGCAUGGUGGCUCACACCUGUAGUCCCAACACUUAGGGAGGCCGAGGCGGGCGGAUCACCUGAGAUCAGGAGUUCAAGACCAGCCUGGCCAACAUGGCGAAUUCCCGUUCUCUACUAAAAAUACAAAAAAUGUGUGGGGUGUGGUGGCAGGAGCCUGUAAUCCUAGCUACUCAGGAGGCUGAGGCAGGAGAAUCGCUUGAGCCCAGGAGGCGGAGAUUGCAGUGAGCCGAGAUCGUGUCACUGCACUCCAGCCUGGGUGACAAGAGUGAGACUCCGUCUCCAAAAAAAAAAAAAAAGAAUUUAUUAACCUGGUUGGUUAAUAAAUUGUGUGGUCCCUGCCGGGCGUGGUGGCUCACGCCUGUAAUCCCAGCACUUUGGGAGGCCGAGACGGGCAGAUCACGAGGUCAGGAGAUCGAGACCAUCCUGGCUAACACGGUGAAACCCCGUCUCUACUAAAAAUACAAAAAAUUAGCCAGGCGUGGUGGCGGGCACCUGUAGUUCCAGCUACUUGGGAGGCUGAGGCAGGAGAAUGGCGUGAACCCAGGAGGCGGAGCUUGCAGUGAGCCGAGAUUGUGCCACUGCACUCCAGCCUGGGCCACGGCCACAGAGCGAGACUCUGUCUCAAAAAAAAAAAAAAAUUAAAAUUGUGUGGUCCCUUUCCAUGUCACAGAGUCUGCUUUUGGCUCAGAGUCUGUAUCUAGCCUGUGUCAGGAUAUUGCCUGUUCUUCCCACCUUGACUUCCAGAGCAGCCAUCGCUGGUGAGCUUUAGUUCUCCUUAGGGUUCCAAGGCAUUAGAAGUAAGAGUGUAGCUUGGAAACCAACUUCUGUGAUUUAGGAAAGCUGUCUCUUUCCUAAGGUAAUAGGGGGUUUAUUUCAUUUAGGCCCCAGUUGGUAGGUUUUAAAAUAAUUUAUAAAGUGUUUUAAUAAUUUGGUUGUCUUUUUUACCUUGCUAAACCAAGCCUCUAAAAACUCAAAUUAUUCCCUUGAUAAAUUUUUAUAAUGGAAAAGCAA